GCAAAUUCGUGGAUCGCUCCGCUGAAUCCGCCCGCGCGUCGCCGCCGUCGUCGCCGCCCCCCGUCCCGGCCCCCCUGGGUUCCCUCAGCCCAGCCCUGUCCAGCCCGGUUCCCGGGAGGAUGAAGUUCGUGUACAAAGAAGAGCAUCCGUUCGAGAAGCGCCGCUCUGAGGGCGAGAAGAUCCGAAAGAAAUACCCGGACCGGGUGCCGGUGAUAGUAGAAAAGGCUCCCAAAGCUCGGAUAGGAGACCUGGACAAAAAGAAAUACCUGGUGCCUUCUGAUCUCACAGUUGGUCAGUUCUACUUCUUGAUCCGGAAGCGAAUUCAUCUCCGAGCUGAGGAUGCCUUGUUUUUCUUUGUCAACAAUGUCAUUCCACCCACCAGUGCCACAAUGGGUCAGCUGUACCAGGAACACCAUGAAGAAGACUUCUUUCUCUACAUUGCCUACAGUGACGAAAGUGUCUACGGUCUGUGAAGCUGCUGCCCCUGAGCUGGAGGGGGGUCUCAUUCUACAAAGAGAGAGGUGGCCCCCCUUUCUUGACCUCCUCCUCCUUCAAGCUCAAACACCACCUCCCUUAUUCAGGACCGGCACUUCUUAAUGUUUGUGGCUUUCUCUCCAGCCUCUCUUAGGAGGGGUAAUGGUGGAGUUGGCAUCUUGUAACUCUCCUUUCUCCUUUCUUCCCCUUUCUCUGCCCGCCUUUCCCAUCCUGCUGUAGACUUCUUGAUUGUCAGUCUGUGUCACAUCCAGUGAUUGUUUUGGUUUCUGUUCCCUUUCUGACUGCCCAAGGGGCUCAGAACCCCAGCAAUCCCUUCCUUUCACUACCUUCUUUUUUGGGGGUAGUUGGAAGGGACUGAAAUUGUGGGGGGAAGGUAGGAGGCACAUCAAUAAAGAGGAAACCACCAAGCUGAACUGAAUUUUGCCUUGUGUUGCUCCCCUCGUCCCGCUGAUUUUAAGUCUUUCCAAGGUGUCAGUGGGUUUCAGUGGUGGGGAAAGAAGAGUACUGGGUACAAGCUGGAGGGAUAGAAGUAUAUUUUGGUUUAUUCUGUUCAUGUUGGGCUUUUCCCUGUCUGCAAAAAGAGGGUGCUUUUGUUGUGAUGGAAUGGAAUACUGAGGAUUAUUUCUUGAAACUUUAGUUUUAUAACACGCAUGUGAAACUAAAUGUUAAAAAUGCUCAUGUAAAAAAAAAUUUUUUUUUACUGUGGGUUCCUGUGGAGAAAGUUCCGAAGUACCUGCUUUAGGUGAACAUCCACAUUUGCUAGAACAUUCUAACUAAGAUAUUUUCAUGUGUGCAAGCUAGUAAAACGGCUGUUCUCAGUUGCA